CUCUGGGUCGCUCCCGGGCUAAGCGUCGGCAAGUUCUGUAGAGAAACUCGGGCAACCUUUGGUCAAGCGGCCCAGGAAGGGCGGGGCUUGGAGGCCUCGUUCUGCGCAUGCGCCGAAGGGGCGUGGCGGUCGCACCUGCGCGAGUUGGGGGAAGGAGGAGGGGCGAGGUGACGCAGGCGUAAUAAUAGAGAAGGUGCCAGAAAGAUCCAAAACAAGUGGCUGCGGCCGUCGCCCAGGAGUCAUCGGACGCCAGAAUCUGGCCGGGUUCUGAGCUUGUUCCGCCUCCCUCCCCCGGGAAUGGCGCUAUCCGGGUCGACCCCGGCCCCGUGCUGGGAGGAGGAUGAGUGCCUGGACUACUACGGGAUGCUGUCGCUUCACCGUAUGUUCGAGGUGGUGGGCGGGCAACUGACCGAGUGCGAGCUGGAGCUCCUGGCCUUUCUGCUGGAUGAGGCUCCUGGCGCCGCCGGAGGCUUAGCCCGGGCCCGCAGCGGCCUAGAGCUCCUGCUGGAGCUGGAGCGCCGCGGGCAGUGCGACGAGAGCAACCUGCGGCUGCUGGGGCAACUCCUGCGCGUGCUGGCCCGCCACGACCUGCUGCCGCACCUGGCGCGCAAGCGGCGCCGGCCAGUGUCUCCAGAACGCUAUAGCUAUGGCACCUCCAGCUCUUCAAAGAGGACAGAGGGUAGCUGCCGUCGCCGUCGGCAGUCAAGCAGUUCUGCAAAUUCUCAGCAGGGUCAGUGGGAGACAGGCUCCCCCCCAACCAAGCGGCAGCGGCGGAGUCGGGGCCGGCCCAGUGGUGGUGCCAGACGGCGGCGGAGAGGGGCCCCAGCCGCACCCCAGCAGCAGUCAGAGCCCGCCAGACCUUCCUCUGAAGGCAAAGUGACCUGUGGCUGUACAAGAAGCAGGGUGCCAGCAUCUGCUUCUGUUGAGGACCUCCGGAAGCUUCCAUUCAUGGUGGAAGGCCAAGGGGAGCAGGCUUGUCACAUGACAUCCGGCUCCGGGUUCGAGCAGAGUACUGCGAGCAUGGGCCAGCCUUGGAGCAGGGCGUGGCAUCCCGGCGGCCCCAGGCGCUGGCGCGGCAGCUGGACGUGUUUGGGCAGGCCACCGCAGUGCUGCGCUCAAGGGACCUGGGCUCUGUGGUUUGUGACAUCAAGUUCUCAGAGCUCUCCUAUCUGGACGCCUUCUGGGGCGACUACCUGAGUGGCGCCCUGCUGCAGGCCCUGCGGGGCGUGUUCCUGACUGAGGCCCUGCGAGAGGCUGUGGGCCGGGAGGCUGUUCGCCUGCUGGUCAGUGUGGAUGAGGCUGACUAUGAGGCUGGCCGGCGCCGCCUGUUGCUGAUGGAGGAGGAAGGGGGGCGGCGCCCGACAGAGGCCUCCUGAUCCAGGACUGGCAGGAUUGAUCCCACCUCCAAGUCUCCGGGCCACCUUCUCCUGGGAGGACGACCAUCUCUACCCCUAGAGGACUGUCACUCUAGCAUCUUUGAGGACUGCGACAGGACCGGGACAGCAGGCCCCUUGACAGCCCCUCCCACAGGAUGUGGGCUCUGAGGCCUAAACCAUUUCCAGCUGAGUUUCCUUCCCAGACUCCUCCUACCCCCAGGUGUGCCCCCUUAGCCUCCGGAGGCGGGGGCUGGGCCUGUAUCUCAGAAGGGAGGGGCACAGCUACACACUCACCAAAGGCCCCCCUGCACAUUGUAUCUCUGAUCUUGGGCUGUCUGCACUGUCACAGGUGCACACACUCGCUCAUGCUCACACUGCCCCUGCUGAGAUCUUCCCUGGGCCUCUGCCCUGGCCUGCUUCCCAGCACACACUUCUUUGGCCUAAGGGCUUCUCUCUCAGGACCUCUAAUUUGACCACAACCAACCUGGGCUUCAGCCACAUCAGUGGGCACUGGAGCUGGGGUGCACAUGGGGCCUGCUCACCUUGCCCACACAUCUCCAGCCAGCCAGGGCCCUGCCCAGCUUCAAUUUACAGACCUGACUCUCCUCACCUUCCCCCCUGCUGUCCAGAGCUGAACAUAGACUUGCACUUGGAUGUCACCUGGAGUGUCACAUGGGAGUGUUAUGGCAGCAUCAUACCAAGGCCUACUGUUGCACAUGGGGCCAAAACCAGUAAACAGCCACCUUCUUGGAAAGGGAAUGCAAAGGCUUUGGGGGUGAUGGAAAAGACCUUUUACAAAUGAUACCAAUUAAACUGCCCUGGAAAGGGCAUAGGUGGGCA